GCCCUCCCCUUUGUGUCGCCAUGGCGGCGGCAGCGGCGACGAGAACGGCGAGCGAGGGGUCGAGCGCGGCCGGGGCCUGAGGAGGCUACGCGACCAUGGUGGCACGCAGCACUGACAGCCUGGAUGGCCCAGGGGAGGGCUCGGUGCAGCCUCUACCCACUGCUGGGGGGCCCAGUGUGAAGGGGAAGCCUGGGAAGAGGCUCUCAGCUCCUCGAGGCCCCUUCCCGCGGCUGGCUGACUGCGCCCAUUUCCACUACGAGAACGUUGACUUUGGCCACAUUCAGCUCCUGCUGUCUCCAGACCGUGAAGGGCCCAGCCUCUCUGGAGAGAAUGAGCUGGUGUUCGGGGUGCAGGUGACCUGUCAGGGCCGUUCCUGGCCGGUUCUCCGGAGUUACGAUGACUUUCGUUCCCUGGAUGCCCACCUCCACCGGUGCAUAUUUGACCGGAGGUUCUCCUGCCUUCCGGAGCUUCCCCCGCCCCCCGAGGGUGCCAGGGCUGCCCAGAUGCUGGUGCCACUGCUGCUGCAGUACCUGGAGACACUGUCAGGACUGGUGGACAGUAACCUCAACUGCGGGCCUGUGCUCACCUGGAUGGAGCUGGACAAUCACGGCCGGCGACUGCUCCUCAGUGAGGAGGCGUCACUCAAUAUCCCUGCAGUGGCGGCCGCCCAUGUGAUCAAACGGUAUACAGCCCAGGCGCCAGAUGAGCUGUCCUUUGAGGUGGGAGACAUUGUCUCGGUGAUCGACAUGCCACCCACAGAGGAUCGGAGCUGGUGGCGGGGCAAGCGAGGCUUCCAGGUCGGGUUCUUCCCCAGUGAGUGUGUGGAACUCUUCACAGAGCGGCCAGGUCCGGGCCUGAAGGCGGCAGAUGCCGAUGGCCCCCCAUGUGGCAUCCCGGCUCCCCAGGGUAUCUCGUCUCUGACCUCAGCUGUGCCACGGCCUCGUGGGAAGCUGGCCGGCCUGCUCCGCACCUUCAUGCGCUCCCGCCCUUCUCGGCAGCGGCUGCGGCAGCGGGGAAUCCUGCGACAGAGGGUGUUUGGCUGCGAUCUUGGCGAGCACCUCAGCAACUCAGGCCAGGAUGUGCCCCAGGUGCUGCGCUGCUGCUCCGAGUUCAUUGAGGCCCACGGGGUGGUGGAUGGGAUCUACCGGCUCUCAGGCGUGUCUUCCAACAUCCAGAGGCUUCGGCACGAGUUUGACAGUGAGAGGAUCCCGGAGCUGUCUGGCCCUGCAUUCCUGCAGGACAUCCACAGCGUGUCCUCCCUCUGCAAGCUCUACUUCCGAGAGCUUCCGAACCCUCUGCUCACCUACCAGCUCUAUGGGAAGUUCAGUGAGGCCAUGUCAGUGCCUGGGGAGGAGGAGCGUCUGGUGCGGGUGCACGAUGUCAUCCAGCAGCUGCCCCCACCACAUUACAGGACCCUGGAGUACCUGCUGAGGCACCUGGCCCGCAUGGCGAGACACAGUGCCAACACCAGCAUGCAUGCCCGCAACCUGGCCAUUGUCUGGGCACCCAACCUGCUACGGUCCAUGGAGCUGGAGUCAGUGGGAAUGGGUGGCGCGGCGGCGUUCCGGGAAGUUCGGGUGCAGUCGGUGGUGGUGGAGUUUCUGCUCACCCAUGUGGACGUCCUGUUCAGCGACACCUUCACCUCCGCCGGCCUCGACCCUGCAGGCCGCUGCCUGCUCCCCAGGCCCAAGUCCCUUGCGGGCAGCUGCCCCUCCACCCGCCUGCUGACGCUGGAGGAAGCCCAGGCACGCACCCAGGGCCGGCUGGGGACGCCCACGGAGCCCACAACUCCCAAGGCCCCGGCCUCACCUGCGGAAAGACGGCCUCCUGUUUCUCCCCCAAACCGCAGGAGGAAAGGGGAGAGAGGGGAGAAGCAGCGGAAGCCAGGGGGCAGCAGCUGGAAGACGUUCUUUGCACUGGGCCGGGGCCCCAGUGUCCCUCGAAAGAAGCCCCUGCCCUGGCUGGGGGGCACCCGUGCCCCACCGCAGCCUUCAGGCAGCAGACCCGACACCGUCACACUGAGAUCUGCCAAGAGCGAGGAGUCUCUGUCAUCGCAGGCCAGCGGGGCUGGCCUCCAGAGGCUGCACAGGCUGCGGCGACCCCACUCCAGCAGCGACGCUUUCCCUGUGGGCCCAGCACCUGCUGGCUCCUGCGAGAGCCUGUCCUCGUCCUCCUCCUCCGAGUCCUCCUCCUCUGAGUCCUCCUCUUCCUCCUCUGAGUCCUCAGCAGCUGGGCUGGGGGCACUCUCUGGGUCUCCCUCACACCGUACCUCAGCCUGGCUAGAUGAUGGUGAUGAGCUGGACUUCAGCCCACCCCGCUGCCUGGAGGGACUCCGGGGGCUGGACUUUGAUCCCUUAACCUUCCGCUGCAGCAGCCCCACCCCAGGGGAUCCCGCACCUCCCGCCAGCCCAGCACCCCCCGCCCCUGCCUCUGCCUUCCCACCCAGGGUGACCCCCCAGGCCAUCUCGCCCCGGGGGCCCACCAGCCCCGCCUCGCCUGCUGCCCUAGACAUCUCAGAGCCCCUGGCUGUAUCAGUGCCACCCGCUGUCCUAGAACUGCUGGGGGCUGGGGGAGCACCUGCCUCAGCCACCCCAACACCAGCUCUCAGCCCCGGCCGGAGCCUGCGCCCCCAUCUCAUACCCCUGCUGCUGCGAGGAGCCGAGGCCCCGCUGACUGACGCCUGCCAGCAGGAGAUGUGCAGCAAGCUCCGGGGAGCCCAGGGCCCACUCGGUCCUGAUAUGGAGUCACCACUGCCACCCCCUCCCCUGUCUCUCCUGCGCCCUGGGGGUGCCCCACCCCCGCCCCCUAAGAACCCAGCACGCCUCAUGGCCCUGGCCCUGGCUGAGCGGGCUCAGCAGGUGGCCGAGCAACAGAGCCAGCAGGAGUGUGGGGGCACCCCACCUGCUUCCCAAUCCCCCUUCCACCGCUCGCUGUCUCUGGAGGUGGGCGGGGAGCCCCUGGGGACCUCAGGGAGUGGGCCACCUCCCAACUCCCUAGCACACCCGGGUGCCUGGGUCCCGGGACCCCCACCCUACUUACCAAGGCAACAAAGUGAUGGGAGCCUGCUGAGGAGCCAGCGGCCCAUGGGGACCUCAAGGAGGGGACUCCGAGGCCCUGCCCAGGUCAGUGCCCAGCUCAGGGCAGGUGGCGGGGGCAGGGAUGCGCCAGAGGCAGCAGCCCAGUCCCCAUGUUCUGUCCCCUCACAGGUUCCUACCCCCGGCUUCUUCUCCCCAGCCCCCAGGGAGUGCCUGCCACCCUUCCUCGGGGUCCCCAAGCCAGGCUUGUACCCCCUGGGCCCCCCAUCCUUCCAGCCCAGUUCCCCAGCCCCAGUCUGGAGGAGCUCUCUGGGCCCCCCUGCACCACUCGACAGGGGAGAGAACCUGUACUAUGAGAUCGGGGCAAGUGAGGGGUCCCCCUAUUCUGGCCCCACCCGCUCCUGGAGUCCCUUUCGCUCCAUGCCCCCCGACAGGCUCAAUGCCUCCUACGGCAUGCUUGGCCAAUCACCCCCACUCCACAGGUCCCCCGACUUCCUGCUCAGCUACCCGCCAGCCCCCUCCUGCUUUCCCCCUGACCACCUUGGCUACUCAGCCCCCCAGCACCCUGCUCGGCGCCCUACACCGCCUGAGCCCCUCUACGUCAACCUAGCUCUAGGGCCCAGGGGUCCCUCACCUGCCUCUUCCUCCUCCUCUUCCCCUCCUGCCCACCCCCGAAGCCGUUCAGAUCCCGGUCCCCCAGUCCCCCGCCUUCCCCAGAAACAACGGGCACCCUGGGGACCCCGUACCCCUCAUAGGGUGCCGGGUCCCUGGGGCCCUCCUGAGCCUCUCCUGCUCUACAGGGCAGCCCCGCCAGCCUACGGAAGGGGGGGCGAGCUCCACCGAGGGUCCUUGUACAGAAAUGGAGGGCAAAGAGGGGAGGGGGCUGGUCCCCCACCCCCUUACCCCACUCCCAGCUGGUCCCUCCACUCUGAGGGCCAGACCCGAAGCUACUGCUGAGCACCAGCUGGGAGGGGCCGUCCUUCCUUCCCUUCACCCUCACUGGAUCUUGGCCCAACCAAAUCCCUUGUUUUGUAUUUUCUUGAACCCCGACCACUACCCCAGGUUUCUAACUUUGUAACUUGCUUCUGAUGUGGGUCCCUAACCUAUAAUCUCAGCUUCCCUACCCUGGACUGAAGGGUCUGCCCAUCCCCCCACCACCCUCCAUCCUGGGGGCCCUCGCACAAAUCUGGGGUGGGAGGGGCUAGGCUGACCCCAUCCUCCUCUCCCUCCAGGAGCCCCCAGCAUGUCCUGACCUGUGCACGGGGAUGGGGGGACAACUCCUACCCUUCUUUCCCCACAUGCCCCACUAAACCAUCUGACAACAUUAAUGAAUAAAAUGGUGAAAAUGUG